UCACUCACUCACACACCUCCCCCAGCUCACCUCCUCCCCACUCCAGCAUGGCCGCCUCCACCAUGUCCAUCUGCUCCAGCGCCUGCACCAACUCCUGGCAGGUGGACGACUGCCCAGAGAGCUGCUGUGAGCUCCCCUGCGGCACCCCCAGCUGCUGUGCCCCAGCCCCCUGCCUGACCCUGGUCUGCACCCCAGUGAGCUGUGUGUCCAGCCCCUGCUGCCAGGCGGCCUGUGAGCCCAGCGCCUGCCAAUCAGGCUGCACCAGCUCCUGCACGCCCUCGUGCUGCCAGCAGUCUAGCUGCCAGCCGGCUUGCUGCACCUCCUCCCCCUGCCAGCAGGCCUGCUGCGUGCCCGUCUGCUGCAAGCCUGUGUGCUGUGUGCCCGUCUGCUGUGGGGCUUCUUCAUGCUGCCAGCAGUCUAGCUGCCAGCCAGCUUGCUGUGCCUCUUCCUCCUGCCAGCAGUCCUGCCGUGUGCCUGUCUGCUGCAAAGCUGUGUGCUGCGUGCCCACCUGCUCUGAGUCAUCCUCUUCAUGCUGCCAGCAGUCUAGCUGCCAGCCGGCUUGCUGCACCUCCUCCCCGUGUCAGCAGUCCUGCUGUGUGUCCGUCUGCUGCAAGCCUGUCUGCUGCAAGUCCAUCUGCUGUGUACCUGUUUGCUCUGGGGCUUCCUCUCCGUGCUGCCAGCAGUCUAGCUGCCAGCCAGCUUGCUGCACCUCCUCCUGCUGCAGACCCUCCUCCUCUGUGUCCCUCCUCUGCCGCCCCGUGUGCUCCCGCCCAGCCUCCUGCAGCUUUUCCUCAGGCCAAAAGUCUAGCUGCUGAUGGCCAUGUCCCCCAGGGCCAGCCGGGCUCAGGCCCCACCUCCCUGCCAGUCCUUGGACCUCCCAGCCCACCCAGCCUCAGCACAGCUCAGCACAGAAGGAGCAGCCCCAGCCACAGCCGCCCAGCCCCGGGGUCUCAGAUGCUCACUGGCUCCUCUCUGACCUCCCGCCGGGCGGGCGAGCCCUGGCUUCUCCUCACGGUGCUUCCUGGCUGCAGACCACAACCCUCCGCUGGUCGCUGGUCGCUGGUUGGGGAUGGGCCCUCCUGACCUGGGUCUCACCCCCAGGAGCGUCACCCUCUGCCUCUGAGCACCAAUAAAGCGUCUGCGGCCCCA